AGCGGAGGCCGGGAGGACCAGGAACCCAGGAGAGCAUGGCCACGCUGCGCCGGCUUCGGGAGGCGCCGCGGCACUUACUGGUUUGCGAGAAAUCCAACUUCGGCAACCACAAGUCGCGCCACCGGCAUCUUGUGCAGACGCACUACUAUAACUACAGGGUUUCAUUUCUCAUUCCUGAAUGUGGGAUACUAUCGGAAGAACUGAAAAACCUGGUCAUGAACACUGGACCCUAUUACUUUGUGAAGAAUUUACCUCUUCAUGAAUUAAUUACACCUGAAUUCAUCAGUACCUUUAUAAAGAAAGGUUCUUGCUAUGCACUAACAUACAAUACACAUAUUGAUGAAGAUAAUACUGUUGCCCUGCUACCAAAUGGGAAAUUAAUUUUGUCACUGGAUAAAGACACUUAUGAAGAAACUGGACUUCAGGGUCAUCCAUCUCAGUUUUCUGGCAGAAAAAUUAUGAAAUUUAUUGUUUCCAUUGAUUUGAUGGAAUUAUCCUUAAACUUGGAUUCUAAGAAGUAUGAAAGAAUAUCUUGGUCUUUCAAAGAAAAGAAGCCAUUGAAAUUUGAUUUUCUUUUGGCUUGGCAUAAAACAGGUUCAGAAGAAUCGACAAUGAUGUCAUAUUUUUCCAAGUACCAAAUUCAGGAGCAUCAGCCAAAAGUAGCACUGAGCACGUUGAGAGAUCUCCAGUGCCCAGUGCUGCAGAGCAGCGAGCUGGAGGGAACGCCAGAGGUGUCCUGCCGGGCUCUGGAGCUCUUCGACUGGCUCGGCGCCGUCUUCAGUAAUGUCGACCUAAAUAAUGAGCCUAAUAAUUUCAUAUCAACCUAUUGCUGUCCUGAGCCAAGCACAGUGGUGGCAAAAGCUUAUUUGUGUACAAUCACUGGCUUCAUACUUCCAGAGAAGAUCUGUCUCCUAUUGGAACAUCUCUGGUAACUGGCAGAAGCAAAACAGAUUGUCUUUGGAGGAACUCGGAGAGUUUCAAGGAAUGUAAGUUCAUAGAAAAAAAUCACAAGUGUAAAAUAGACAAGAACCAGCAGAAACAAGGGGCAGAAGCAGGCCGUUAAGUCUCAGAAAGACUUAAGAUGUUAAAGUUAGCAAGCACAUCCAUAAAGUAUGCUUUAUGCUUACAGAAAUAAGGAGGGUUAAAUGGCAUGAGUAUAAGAACAACGAAGCAGAUUGUAAAAAGUGCCAAACAAAUCUAGGAAUGAAAAAUAUAAUUGAAAUUGCAAAUUCCACUGGUUGGUUUAACAGCAGACUAGACGCCACUGAAAAUAGAAUAAUGGAUAUGAAGAAAUUAAGAUCUUUUCAAAUUUGCAAAAGCUGAAAGACUGUCACCCACAGGUCUGCACUGCAAGAAAAGUUAAAGGAUGUCCUUUGGGCAGAAGGAAAAUGCCUGCCUUCUGAAGGAAAUAAGCACUGGAAAUAGUAACAACAUGGGUAAAUGUAGCAUUUAUUAUUUAAACCUCUUUAAAAGACAGUUAUUUAAAUAAAAGUCAUAGUGUAGGAUUUAUAAUAUAUGUAAGAGUAAAAUGGAUGACCACAAUAGCUUGAAGAUUAGGAGAGGAGAAUCAUGCUAUUGUAAAGUUCUCAUACACAAGGUGACGUGCUACCAUUUGAAGAUAGAGUGUGAUAAGUUACAGAUAUGUGCUGUAAACCCUAAAGCAGCUGCUAAAAUGACAUACCAAAAAAUCAUACCUAUUAAACUAUCAAAAGAUAAAAUGGAAUUAUUUUAAAAACUUGAUUCAUCAAAAAGAAGACAGAAAAAGAGGUAAAAGGGAAUAAAGAACAGUUAGGAUGAAUCGAAGACAAGUAGCAAGAUGAGAGACUCAACCUAAGCAUAUCAAUAAUCACAUUAAAUGUGAAUAGUGUGAACACCACCAAUUAAAAGGCAUAGAUUUUCAGACUGGAUUGAAAAAAACAUGACCUAAUUAUAUUCUGCCUACAAGAAAUGUACUUUAAAUAGAAAGAUACAAAUACUUAAAGGAUGGAAAAAAGAUAUGCUAACACUAGUUACAUGAAAAUUGAAGUGGCUAUAUUAAUCAAAAUAGAGCAAAAAGUAAUUCCCAGCAUAUUAGUCAAUUCUCGCACUGCCAUAAAGAAAUAUCUGAGACUGGGUAGCUUAUAAAGAAAAGAGGUUUAAUUGGCUCACAUUUCUUCUUCUUCUUUUUUUUUUUUUUUUUUUUGAGACAGAGCCUCCCUCUGUUGCCCAGGAUGGACUGCAGUGGCGCAAUCUCGGCUCACUGCAACCUCCACCUCCUGGGUUCAAAUGAUUCUCCUGCCUCAGCCUCUUGAGUAGCUGGGAUUACAGGCAUGCGCCACCAUGCCUGGCUAGUUUUUUUUUGUUUCGUUUUUUUGUUUUUGUUUGUUUUUCUUUUUUUAGUAGAAACAGGGUUUCACCUUAUUGGCCAGGCUGGUCUCGAACUCCUGACCUCGUGAUCUCUCCACCUCAGCCUCCCAAAGUGCUGGGAUUACAGGCAUGGGCCACCACACCUGGCCUAAUUGGCUCACGUUUCUGCAGGCUGUGCAGGAAGCACAGUGGGCAUCUGCCUGGCUUCUGGGGAGGCCUCAGGAAAACUCAAUCAUGGCGGAAGGUGAAAGAGAAGCAUGGCCAGAGCAGGAGGGAGGGGUGUGGGAGGUACCACACACUUUUAAACAACCAGAUCUUGUGAGAAUUCUAUCACUAGAAGAGCACUAAAUGGGGGAAUCCACCCCCAUGAGCCAAUCACCUCCCACCAGGCCCCAACUCCAACACUGGGGAUUACAAUUUGACAUGAGAUUUGGGCAGGGACACAGACCCAAACCGUAUCACCCAGGAUUAAAGAAAGUUAUUUCAUACUGACAACACACACCUCAUAACAAAGCUUCAAAACACAUAAAGCAAGAACAACUAGAACUUCAAGGAGACAUAGAUCAACCCACUAUUAUCAGACGUUAAUACCCCACCCUCAAUAAUUGACAGAACAAGUAGGCAGAAAAUCAAUAAGAAUAAUAAAGUAGACUUCAGCAAUUUUAUCAAUCAACUUGACCCGAUUGACAUUUACAGGACAUUGCAUCUUACAAUAGCAGAAAAUUUUUCUUGAGAAAAUGGAGAAACAACUCAAUUUUGUUUCUUGAGAAAUAACUUGAGAAAAAUUUUUAGCUGUUCAAACAAAAAUCAUAGUACGGGAUUUAUAAUAUAUGUAAAAGUAAAGUGGGUUAAGAGUUUUUCGCAAGUACACAUGGAACAUUUAUAGAGAUGGACUACAUUAUAGACCAUUUAAAAAGUCUCAAAUUCAAAACAUUUGUCACAUAAAGUAUGUUGUCUGGCCACAACGGAAUUAAAUUAGAAAUCAAUAGCAGAAACUAGAAAAGAGAAAAACUCAAAGUAAGCAGAAGAAAAGGAAUAAUAAAGGUCAAAGUGGGACUUAAUGAAAUUUUUAAAAUAGAGAAAAAUGAAUGAAUCAAAAUUUGGGGAGUUUGGGGGGGAAAUUUUUUUAAAUUGAGAAAUCUCCAGCCAGGUACAUAUAUCAGGGAAAAAAGAAACAAGACACAAGUUACCAAUACUAGGAAUGAGAGAGGUGGCAUCACUGAAGAGCCUACAGAUAGAAAAGGAUAGUAAGGAAAUAUUAGGAACACCUUUAUAGCAAUAAAUUCAACAUAGAUGAAAUUGACAAAUCCUUUGAAAGGCACAAAUUACCAAAGCUCACCCAAGAAGAAGUAGAUGAUCUGAAUAGCCCUAUAUCUGUUAAAGAAGUUGAAAUUACAGUUUAAAAACAUGUAACGAAAAUCUAGGGCUAGGCGUGGUGGCUCGCACCUGUAUUCCCAGCAUGUUGGGAAGUUGAGGUGGGAGGAUCACUUGAAGCCAGGAGUUCAAGGACAGACUGGACAACAUAGCGAGAUUCCAAAAAAAAAAAAAAAAAAAUUAGCCAGGCAUGGUAGCACAUGCCUGUAGUCCUAGCUACUUGAGAGGCUGAGGCAGGAUGAUUGCUUGAGCCUAGGAAUUGAAGGCUGCGGUGAGCAAUGAUCACACCACUGCACUCCAGCCUGGCUGACAAAUCAAGGCCCUGACUCAAAGAAAGGGAGAGAAGGAGAGAGAGAGGAAGAAAUAUUUUCCACCUCAUUAUCUGAGGCCAGAAUUAUCCUAGUGCCAAAAUUAUCCUAGGACCCUGGCCAAACAAACAUGCUACCAGGAAAGAAAACUACAGAUCAACAUUUCUCAUGAACAUAGGGUAAAAUUCUAAGCCAGUUUAUCAAAUUGAGUCCUACAAGAUAAGAAACAGGUAAUAAAACAUGAUCAAGAGGGAAUAUCCAAGGAGUGUAGGGUUGACUUAACAUUUGAAAAAUCAAUCAAUAUAAUUCAUUGUAUAAACAAGCUAAAAAAGAAUAAUCAUAUAAUCAAUCAAUACAGAAAGGCAUUUGACAAAAUCCAGCAUUCAUUACUGAUAAUCAAGAAGGUUAGGAAUAAACAACACUUCUUCAAUCUGAUCAAGGGCAUCUACAAAAACCCUACAGCUAACAUCACACUUAAUUGUGAAAGACAAUAUUCCCCACCUUCCCAACGUCAGGAACAAAUCAGGGAUGCCUGCUUUUACCGCCUCUGUUCAACAUUGUACUGAAGGCUUUAGACUGUGCAAUCAGAGAACAAACAGAAAUAAUGGACAUCCAGGUUGGAAAGAAAGAAAGAAAAAUGUAUUCACAGAUGACAUGAUUAUUUAUGCAAAAUUCAGCGGACUCUACAAAUGAGCUACUAGAACAAAUAAGUGAGUUUGUCAAGGUUGCAGGAUACAGAGUAGUGUACAAAAAUCAGUUGUAUAUGGUAGCAAUGAAAAAUUGAUAAUUGAAACAAAAAAUCAACAUUUGCAAUCACAUAAACAAUACUACCUUUGCAAUAGCAUAAAUACCUGGGAUAAGUCUGACCAAAAAAAUGAGAAAAAUACUGUACACUGAAAACUACAAAAUACUGAUAUGAUAAAGAGACCUAAAUAGAUGAUAUACCUUGUUCAUGGGUCAGAAGACUCAAUAUUGUGAAGAUGUCAUGUCAUAUUCCCAAAAUAUAGAUUCAAUAUAGAUUUAAUACAAUCACAAUCAAAAUCCCAGCAGCCUAUGUGUGUGUGUGUGUGUGUGUAAAAUGACAAACUGAUUCUAAAAUGUUUGUAGAACUUCAAAGGACCUAGAGUAGCCAAACAACUUCACAAAAGAAGAACCAAGUUAGACGACUAAUAUUACUAGAUUUUUAAGGAGUUAUUCUAAAGCAACAGUAAUCAAGACAGUGUGGUAUUGACAUGAAGGAUAUACCAAUAGAUCAAUGAUAUAGGAUUUGUGUCCAGAAUGUAAAGUACUUUCAAAACUCAGCAAUAAGAAAACAAACAAACCAAAUGGAAAAUGAAGGAAAGACAUCAACAGACAUUUUACCAAAGAGUCCACUUAAACUGCAAAUAAAUGAGUGAAAAGAUGUUCUAACAUCAUUAACCAUUAGGAAAAAGGCAACUUAAAAUCAUGAUAUCACUAACUCCUAUUAGAAUGGUUACAAAGGCAAAUUAAAAUCAUGAUAUCACUAACUCCUAUUAGAAUGGUAAAAGAUAGUGAUAACAUCAAAUUCUGACAACUAUGCUGAAAAACUUUAUCUCCCGUAUAUUACUGGCAGUAAUGUAUAAUUUCACAGCCAUUCAGAAAAAUACCUCCCAGUUUACUUAUAAAAGAAAACAUGAAAUUACCAUAUGAUCCAGUAAUUUCACUCUUGGGCAUUUAUCCUGGGAAAUGAACUUAUGUUCACACAAAAACCCAUACUCAAAUGUUCAUAGCAGCUUUAUGUGUAAUGAGCAAGACCUAGGAAAAAAACAAAUGUCCUUCAGUGCGUGAAUGGUUAAGCAAAUUGUGAUCCAUGAAAUACUGCUUAACAAUAAAAAGGAGCAAGUUAUUAACACACCCAAUAACUUGGAAGGAUCUCAAGGGAAUUAUAUGGAGUGAAAAAAAACCCAGACCAAAAAGUUACUAUUGUAUGAUUCCAUUUAUAUAACAUCCUUGAAAUGAAAAAAUUGUAGAAAUGGAGACCAGAUUAGUGGUUGCCUGAGAUUAGGGAUGUUGGGGGUGGGGAGGGGUCAGUGUGGCUGUAACAGGGCAAUAAAAAGGAUCAUCAUGGUGAUGGAA